AGAACCAGAGAGGGCUCGGCUGUAUCGAUGUAGGAAACUGUAGCCCCUCAGGAGGCCCUCUGGCAAGACCUCCCCUUCCUGCCCCCACCCCCAGUAGUUAUGGGGCCUGGGGUGCUGGGGCUGAGGGGUUCCAAGAGUCAAGGGAAGCACUGGGAAAUCACCCCUUUUUAUCUAAAGGCCCUACUUUGGGGUUUUUCCCCUGUACCCUGGUCUUCCCCUACCCUGACCCUGGGAGGAAGCUGAAAGAAGCUUCUUUCUGGGCACCUUUUGCCCCAGAGCCUCAGCCUGUCUGGACCAGGUGGGCAGCAGGGCCCAGGGUGUGGGCAGCUGACCCGGAGGGGUGGGAUUUGGGGGUCAGGGCCUGUACAGGGAACCCCUUGUCCUCUCCCUGAGCUGGGUGUGGGUUUGCAAGGAGACAUGUGACCCAGACCAACCCUGGGAGCAGCAGGGCGCCUGCUGUCUGGCCACUCUUACUAGGACUGCUGUGGCACUUCCUCCCCUAGUGGGUCCCUGGUGCCCAUGAAUUGCAGCUCCUGGGUGGUGGUGGGGGCACUGUCUCCUGGGACUCCAGCAUGGCCCUGGGGUGAGCUGUGGGCUUACCCCACCUCAGCAGGUCCUCUAGGGCUGCCCACUGGAUGCUUCGCUGCCUCACACAAUUGUAGGGACUUCCUCAGGCUGUUGGAUUUCCCCACCUUCCGGGGCUCAGGUCCAUUGACUUAGGUCUAGGGCUCCAUACAUUUCACCCAGAGACUCCGGAGCCUGGCAGGCAGACCUGUUCUGACACCGAACUUCCAAAGUCAUGGGCCUUGAUUGGGGUGGUCUGAAUUAGACCUAGCCCUUUUCUGGGCAGAAGGGAGCUUCUAGGAGGAUGGAUGCUGUUCGGGUUAGAGCUCGUGUGGACCUAGCUGCAGGCAAAAGCCUUGAGGCUGAGUCCCUUCUGUGGCAUGGUGGACAGACUCUCGCUCAUCACAGCCGGGCUUGUCACGGGAGCUCCUCCUCCACACCCCUCCCUAAGCUGCCUGUAUGGACGCGGCCCUCUGACACUGAGGUCGGAGUUAUCAUUUCAAAACCUUGCUCUGUAUUAAACAGCCGUGUUGGGCAGGGCCAGACUGCUGGACUGACAGUAGGGGGCAGGCAGCCGGACCCUCUGAGCUCCCCAACGGCACCAGCGCCUGCACGGCCUCAGCCCAGGGGGUCAUUAGGGAAGCUCUCCCCGAUUCUGUGCAGACAGAGCUUCCUCUGUCCACCCUUGCUCGGCCAGAAUUGUGUGCCGCUGGUGACUGGCACCCCUCUAUUCUAGGGCCAAGGCCUCUCAGGGGUCUACAGAUACAACUAUGGGUGGGUGCACACCCAUGUUAUAAACCACACUAAAUGCACAAAAACUGUCUGCAAGUUUGGGGUGCGGGGAACAGCUCUGGGUGGGAGGUUGGAAAUUUGGUCUGGGGGACCCACUCGGCUCCCUCCCUCAGCCCACAGUGAGUCUGGUUUCUGAGUUGUCCCGGUCUAGCCACUUUCGUUUCCCCUGGGGCCGGGUGGAGGCUGGGGCAGAAAGCGGAACUGAGCCCGCGUGUUCUGAGGCCAGGGCAGGGCUGGAGCGUUCUGAACACCUCCCCGUCCCAGCCCCUGGGCCAGGCAAGGGCCGGCCUUACCUCUCCUGGGUUGGUGGCAGCAGAGCUGGGCUCUGAGGGAGGCCUGCAAUGUGAGACAGUAGCAGCUCAGAGGCGGCACUAGGCAGGUGCAACCCCAAAAGGUACUGGGCAGGGAAUUUCAGGGGAAACUGAGGCUCCAUGCUGCAAGGCCAAAGCAGGCCCAGACACAGGGAGUUCAGCUCGAACGUUUGCUCCUUACUUGCUGACCGACACAUUCACUUCUGAUGGGCUGUGCUGUGUAAUGACCCAGUCCUUUCUGUCUUCCACCCAGGGGUCUCAAGUGAAGGGCCAAGGGCAUGGGUAAGGGGAGGAGAGGGACAGAAGGGGACUCAGGACUGUGGAGAGUUUCCGGUUCUGGGCUGGAGAGGGAGUUGGGCAGGUGAAGGGGAGGAGGCAGGGUCCCUCUGGCCUGACUCCAGGGAGGCAGUGAAGCUGUGGCCUGGGAGGCGGGGCUCGUGCCCCUGGGUAGGUAGCAGUUAGAGCUGUGGCUUCUGUUUCCUGUAGCCUUCCUAACAGGCUCCGGCAGGCGUUAGGGCCUUCCUAAGUGCUACCCGAAUGCGUGUCCAGUGGGAGGAGAAGGGGGAGGACCAAGAACCUAGAUGAAUGGCCCUAGAGAGACCCCUCUGCCAUGAACCAGUCCAUCCCAGUGGCUCCCACCCCACCCCGCCGCGUGCGGCUGAAGCCCUGGCUGGUGGCCCAGGUGAACAGCUGCCAGUACCCAGGGCUUCAAUGGGUCAACGGGGAAAAGAAAUUAUUCUGCAUCCCCUGGAGGCAUGCCACAAGGCAUGGUCCCAGCCAGGACGGAGAUAACACCAUCUUCAAGGCCUGGGCCAAGGAGACAGGGAAAUACACCGAAGGCGUGGAUGAAGCCGAUCCGGCCAAGUGGAAGGCCAACCUGCGCUGUGCCCUUAACAAGAGCCGGGACUUCCGCCUCAUCUACGACGGGCCCCGGGACAUGCCACCUCAGCCCUACAAGAUCUACGAGGUCUGCUCCAAUGGCCCUGCUCCCACAGACUCCCAGCCCCCUGAGGAUUACUCUUUUGGUGCAGGAGAGGAGGAGGAAGAAGAGGAAGAGCUGCAGAGGAUGUUGCCAAGCCUGAGCCUCACAGAUGCAGUGCAGUCUGGCCCCCACAUGACACCCUAUUCUUUACUCAAAGAGGAUGUCAAGUGGCCGCCCACUCUGCAGCCGCCCACUCUGCGGCCGCCUACUCUGCAGCCGCCCACUCUGCAGCCGCCCGUGGUGCUGGGUCCCCCUGCUCCAGACCCCAGCCCCCUGGCUCCUCCCCCUGGCAACCCUGCUGGCUUCAGGGAGCUUCUCUCUGAGGUCCUGGAGCCUGGGCCCCUGCCUGCCAGCCUGCCCCCUGCAGGCGAACAGCUCCUGCCAGACCUGCUGAUCAGCCCCCACAUGCUGCCUCUGACCGACCUGGAGAUCAAGUUUCAGUACCGGGGGCGGCCACCCCGGGCCCUCACCAUCAGCAACCCCCAUGGCUGCCGGCUCUUCUACAGCCAGCUGGAGGCCACCCAGGAGCAGGUGGAACUCUUCGGCCCCAUAAGCCUGGAGCAAGUGCGCUUCCCCAGCCCUGAGGACAUCCCCAGUGACAAGCAGCGCUUCUACACGAACCAGCUGCUGGAUGUCCUGGACCGCGGGCUCAUCCUCCAGCUACAGGGCCAGGACCUUUAUGCCAUCCGCCUGUGUCAGUGCAAGGUGUUCUGGAGCGGGCCUUGUGCCUCAGCCCAUGACUCAUGCCCCAACCCCAUCCAGCGGGAGGUCAAGACCAAGCUUUUCAGCCUGGAGCAUUUUCUCAAUGAGCUCAUCCUGUUCCAAAAGGGCCAGACCAACACCCCACCACCCUUCGAGAUCUUCUUCUGCUUUGGGGAAGAAUGGCCUGACCGCAAACCCCGAGAGAAGAAGCUCAUUACUGUACAGGUGGUGCCUGUAGCAGCUCGACUGCUGCUGGAGAUGUUCUCAGGGGAGCUAUCUUGGUCAGCUGAUAGUAUCCGGCUACAGAUCUCAAACCCAGACCUCAAAGACCGCAUGGUGGAGCAAUUCAAGGAGCUCCAUCACAUCUGGCAGUCCCAGCAGCGGUUGCAGCCUGUGGCCCAGGCCCCUCCUGGAGCAGGCCUUGGUGUUGGCCAGGGGCCCUGGCCUAUGCACCCAGCUGGCAUGCAAUAACAAGGCUGCAGACGGUGACUGGCCCUGGCUUCCUGGGUGGCGGUGCGGACUGAUGUGGAGAUGUGACAGCCCCGAUGAGCACCUGGCUGGCUGCAGGGUCCUACCUCUGGGUUUCCUGGAAGUGGAUUUGGGCCAAGAAGGAGAGGGAGAAAGGCCCGAGCCCCUGCCUUCCCGGGCCUUUCUCUCCUGGGCUGUCUCUGGUCUGGUCAGCCUGGCUCUCGGGAAAUUCAGCCAUGAGCAGGGAAAGAACUCUCCCAACCCUGGGGCCUAGCUGUAUAGGAGGAAUUGCCUAAGGGUGGCCCACUCUUGUGAUUGCCCCAUUUCCUCUGGCAACAAAAGCCAGAGUGUUGUGGGCCAAGUCCCCCCACAGGGCCUCUGCAGGGCAUGGCCCUGAUUUCCCUGGUUUGAGACUCACUUCCUCAUCUCCCUGUCCUCUGAGAUAAUAUGAGUGAGCACUUAGGUAUCAUAUCAGAUGCUCAAGGCUGGCAGCUACCCCCUUCUUGAGAGUCCAAGAACCUGGAGCAGAAAUAAUUUUUAUGUAUUUUUGGAUUAAUGAAUGUUAAAAACAGACUCAGCUGUUUCUUUCCUUUUACUACUACCAGUUGCUCCCAUGCUGCUCCACCAGGCCCUGUUUCGGAUGCCAACUGGCCCACUCCCCAAGCACUUGCCCCCAGCUUGCGACCAUUGGCACUGGGAGGGCCUGGCUUCUGGGCUGAUGGGUCAGUUGGGCCUUCAUAAACACUCACCUGGCUGGCUUUGCCUUCCAGGAGGAAGCUGGCUGAAGCAAGGGUGUGGAAUUUUAAAUGUGUGCACAGUCUGGAAAACUGUCAGAAUCAGUUUUCCCAUAAAAGGGUGGGCUAGCAUUGCAGCUGCAUUUGGGACCAUUCAAAUCUGUCACUCUCUUGUGUAUAUUCCUGUGCUAUUAAAUAUAUCAGGGCAGUGCAUGUAAAUCAUCCUGAUAUAUUUAAUAUAUUUAUUAUAUUGUCCCCCGAGGUGGGGACAGUGAGUGAGUUCUCUUAGUCCCCCCAGAGCUGGUUGUUAAAGAGCCUGGCACCUACCCGCUCUCACUUCAUCUGUGUCAUCUCUGCACACUCCAGCCCACUUUCUGCCUUCAGCCAUUGAGUGGAAGCUGCCCCAGGCCCUUACCAGGUGCAGAUGCCCAAUCUUGAUGCCCAGCCAUCAGAACUGUGAGCCAAAUAAACCUUUUUCUGUAUAAAUUA